ACGUCAGUUUCUGCACUGAAACUCUCAAGAUCAAUGAGCAAAGAGCUUUCUCAGUUCUGCCUUUCAGUUUCUCUCUUCCAGGAAGGAAAACAUUCGAGAGAGCGAGGGAGAGCCGCGGGAGGGCGGGGGGCGGGGGCGCCGGCUGCGGGUGGGAGGAGAGACCGGGAGGCCGGCCGGGCUGCGUCCCGGGUCCCCGCGCCGCGCCGCGACCUGCAGACCCCGCCGCCGCGCUCGGGCCCGUCUCCCACGCCCCCGCCGCCCCGCGCGCCCAACUCCGCCGGCCGCCCCGCCCCGCCCCGCGCGCUCCAGACCCCCGGGGCGGCUGCCGGGAGAGAUGCUGGAAGAAACUUCUUAAAUGACCGCGUCUGGCUGGCCGUGGAGCCUUUCUGGGUUGGGGAGAGGAAAGGAAAGUGGAAAAAACCUGAGAACUUCCUGAUCUCUCUCGCUGUGAGACAUGUCUGAGACUCCUGCUCAGUGUAGCAUUAAGGUUUUUCAUCUGAAAAAUGAGGAUGCUGGUCUCAAUUUCUAAGGCCCCUUCCUGCCCAAACUUACCAGGAGGAAAGAAGCUGGAAGUAGAAAGCAGGAGAGGUUCAAAAAGAAAAUGGGAUGCAUCUCCUUUAGUAAGCUCUACUCUGGAGAAGGACGUUGUCCUUCAAGUACAAACCUUUUCACCGACUUGGGGAGUUUCCCCCCAUUGUAUCCCACCCCAUCUUUUUCUGCCAUCGUGCACUGUGUCGUUUGAAUGUGCUGCUUUGUCAGGGCUGGGGGCUUCCUUGGUGCUCCAGCUUGGCCACAUCCGACACACAGACCACCCCGUCCUCCUUCUGCCUCUAGAGGACCAAGAACAACCCUUGUUCUGAAAGCACCCUGUCCCUGAGCCUGAACACAUGACCCUGGAUGUCAGAAGAUGCUCUUCUCCAUUUCAAUUGCCCAAUUCCAGCUCUGUAAUCAUUAUGUUAAAUGAUACAAGUUUCAAAAAAUAUAUAUUUCUAAUAGACUUUCUAUUAUCUUCCUUAAAUCCACAGUGUCACUUUCAUUCUUACUCCUCAUUUUGGGGUGAAAGUGUAGAAAGAUUGUGGCUUUAGAAUCUGACGUACUUUGCUUCAAAUUCUAGCACCACUGUGUGACAUUGGGAAGCCCGUUCUUUAACCCCACUCAGACUCUGUUUCUCCAUUGAUGAAAUAGAAACAUACAGUAUCUUAUGUGUCUGGCACAUGGAAGGUACUCAGCAUAUUAAUAUUAACCACUUUGGGCUGGGCGCAGUGGCUCACGCCUGUAAUUGCAGCACUUUGGGAGGCCAAAGCAGGCGGAUCAUGAGGUCAGGAGAUUGAGACUAUCCUGGUUAACACAGUGAAACCCUGUCUCUACUAAAAAUACAAAAAUUUAGCCAGGCAUGGUGGCAGGUGCCUGUAGUCCCAGCUGCUCGGGAGGCUGAGGCAGGAGAAUGGCGUGAAUCCGGGAGGCAGAGCUUGCAGUGAGCCGAGAUCGCACCACUGCAGUGCAGCCUGGGAGACAGAGCGAGACUCCAUCUCAAAAAAAAAAAAAAAAAAAAAAAAAUUAACCACUUCAUUCUUCUUAGCCCUUCAAGCCCCCGCACCGUGUUUUCUGACAUAUCAUCUUGUUUUCAUCCUUUCUCUUCGGUUUAAUUCCAGAGGGUACAGAGAAGGUGUAAGUUACAGGUAAAGGAGAGUAAGUGCACUGUGAGUGGGUGCUGAUGAAAUAUCACAACAGGUUCUCAUUCUGACAACUCACACUAGGCCAUGCUUCCCCGGAAUAUUUAUGGAACUAAGUGGAAAAAAGGAUCUUUAGCAAGGAUCCAGCACCCUCAAUGCAGGGAAUGAAAUGUGUUUAUUAUUAGAGCAAUCCAGUUUCCAUACAGCUACCAAUAUACACACACCCACAUACCCUGUUCAGCCAUACUGAAGAGUUUACUUGUAAAUCCAGGCGAAGCUGAUGCUGAGAGGUGGCCCGCUGUACUGAUUUUGUAAAACCAGCAGGAAAACCUCUGCUCGGCCGACCACUUGAUGUUUUAGUUGCAGCCACUAACAUGUUAAUCAAAAGAAGCAAAUACAUGUUUUUCCCUUGAGAAAACAUGGAUAGUGGUGUAACGGAAAUUACCUUGAAUUAUUCCUCCUCAAGUAUCUAUCCAAUCUAGAUAGAUGGAUUAUCUGAUUGCACCAGGAGAUGCAGACCUGGCAGUGGCUACUUCUAUUGCAGCAUCUUUAAAGGAAUCAGAUCUUUGGAUUUCCAUUUUCCCAUUUUUAUUCUUAUUUUCUCCCUGCUAAAAAACAGUUUGCAGAGGCACUUGAAAGUGAUAUAAACUCCAUAGUAGAUAAUAGUUGUACAUGAACAUCGUAUCUUUUAUCAUAUAGUCCCCUAUGUAAUUAGGUGAUAGCUUGAGCCUAGCACAGGUGGCGCUGCUGAGCCAUCUCGGAAAUGACCACAUCUGAACUGGGCGCAGUGGUUCAUGCCUGUAAUCCCCACACUUCGGGAGGCCAAGAUGGGUGGAUUGCUUGAGCUCAGGAGUUCGAGACCAGCCUGGGCAACAUGACGAAACCUCGUCUCUACAAAAAAUAUAAAAAUUAGCUGUGUGUGGUGGUGCUCACCUGUGGUCCCAGCUACCUGGGGGGCUGAGAUGAGCAAAAAAAAAAAAGAAAAAAAAAAAAAGAAGAAGAAGAAAUUACCAUAUCUGUAUGUCUAUACAUAGGUAUGUGGAUUUAUCACAGUGCUGGUACAAGUACUUUUGUCAUUGAUGUUUAUUAAGCUUUUUAUGCUCCAGGCACUAUGCAAAAUUGUAGGGCAUUAUCUCCUCUAAUCCUCAGAAUCUUAUGCAGUAGGGCCGGUGUUGCUAUUACUCCAUUUUAUAGAUGAGGAAACUUAGGCUUGGGGUGUUUAAGUAACUUCUAUGAAGUCACACAGUAAGUGCUAGAGCCAAGAGGCAAAGUAAGCCUGGAUGCUUCCAAGCCGUAGCUCUUAACCACUAUGCUAUACUGCUCAAAAAUAUUUUUAGAACUGAAUGAAGACAUCUAAGGAAAAGGAAAACGUGGUCCCUAAUGGUCUUUUGUGAUAACAAUAUGAAACCUUUCGUCUCUAAAGUGUCAUGGAAGUGAAACUUGAAAGGCUCUGUUCUUCAUCUUCUACUUAUUAAUGGGCAAAAUGUCUUCGUAAUUUAUGGCAUGUGUCCCAAAGGUGCAAAGGUGGCAAGGUGGCCUUUUUUUUUUUUUUUUUUUUUUUUUUACUAAUACUAGGUCCUGCUUCCAAGCCUCCUAUUUCUUCACUUCCCUGUGUACCAGGGUUUACCUGCUGCUUAACCCACCCACCCCACUAUACGUGUCUGUAGUAGACCCACCAACAUUCACAUGGCCACUUCUGCUGAAAGUACCUCCCAGGAUAGAAUAGGGUCACAGACCCCCAAUUGUAUAAGCCUUUGGCUUCUUGAUGUCUCUGCGAGUUACGGUUAUGGGAGUUGGUCUUUGGUGAGAUUAGUGGUGAGAUCAGUGGGUGGCACCUAGGGUGAUUUAUUGAAUAGUAUGGGGUGAGGCUGAAGAGCAAACAUCCACGUAAGUGUUGUCUGUUUUGGAGUUUGAAAAGUUGUCACCCUAAUAAACAAACUACUUAAUUGAACAGCCCUUGCUUGGCGUGAUCAAAGAAAAGACCUAGACUUUGCUAUCAGUAGGCUCUGGGUUCCAGGCCUGGCUUGUCACUUACGAUGAUGAUGAUGAUGAUGAUUUUUUAUUUUUUUGAGAUGGAGUUUCACUCUUGUUGCCCAGGCUGGAGUGCAAUGGCACAAUCUCGGCUCGCCACAACCUCCGCCUCCCGGGUUCAAGCGAUUCUCGUCUCAGCCUCUUGAGUAGCUGGGAUUACAGGCGCCCGCCAGUACGCCUGGCUAAUUUUUGGUAUUUUUAGUAGAAACGGGGUUUCACCAUGUUGCCCAGACUGGUCUCGAACUCCUGACCUCAGGUGAUCCACCCGCCUUGGCCUCCCAAAGUGCGGGGAUUACAGGCGUGAACCAUCGCGCCCGGCCAGCUCGUCGCUUAUUAUGCAAGUUGUAUAACAUUGCUGAAUCCCAAGUUUUUAGUCUUUAAAAUGAGAAUUUAAAUGUCGCCCUUAUUUUGAUUGCUGGGAAGUUUAAAUGAAACAGUGUAUGUGCCUGUCACAUAGUAGUUGACAAUAAAUGAUAGUUUCUUUUCCUUUUCCCUUAAGUAAGUUUUUUUUCCCUCUAGCCUAUAAGCUCCUUAAAGAAGAUAGAGAUUUUCUUUUCUCACUCAUUUCCAUAUUCUCAGCCCUUAGCAGUGCCAGGCACAUAUUUGCUGAAUGAAAGAAAAAUCUUUUACAAAGGUCUUCAGAUCAUUCAUUCACCAGACAAUUGUUGAGUAUCUACAGUGUAUCAGGCACUGUUCUUGGAGCAGGGCAGUCUUAAAAAACACACACAAACAUAGUCUGUGUCCCCUUUUUUAGUCUAACUGGGAGAGAAACAUUACAUAGAUAAUUAGAGCAAUGAACAACUUUGAUCCUUGAGAUGGGAUUUAAAUUUUAAGAGAUAGGUGACAUUUGGUGUCAAGUCUGUCCAGGUAUACUUGAUAUUGUUUUUGAUCAGGUACAAGAAACGGCAAUAUACUGUUAUCUAUAACUGGUUCUGAAAGAUCUGAAAGAGGUGUUUCUAAAGUAUUUUUGAGGAAUGGUGCUGCUUUUUUGGAAUAAGUAUAAAUACAUUGUAAAGUAUCUAUUUCGAGAGGGAACAGACUUGAUGGGAUGGGAUCAUAGUAGGUAAGGUGUUCCAGGAACUUGGAACAUACUGGAAUAAGGCUUAAACACAAGUCACAGAACUGGGUGAUAGGGCGGUGAGCGCAUCUACUGGAGAGGAGAUGGGGCAGGGCUGGCAGCUUGUAGCAAGAUUUUUAUGUAGACAGUUAGACUUCAAACUUCAUCAGUAAGUCAGUAGAUGGCCCUAGGUGGAAACACAGGACAAAAGAUGAAUUUGUGUUGGCACUAGAAAUACUUUGAGCUCAUCUAAUGAGGCUCAUUCAUUCAUUUGGUAAAUACUUCACGAGUGUCCAGUGCAAGCUCUGUUCUAGUUGUAAGGGAUAUGGCAGUGAACAAGGCAGACAAGGUCCCUGUGCCUGCAGAGUUUUGAUGAUAACCUUCCCCCCUGGGUGUGUGGGAGGGCCUGGGGCUCCUGUGUGGUUUGGGGGUCUGAGAGGUGGAUGAAGGUACAGUAGGCCCACAGUCGUGGAAAUCAAAGUCCAAGCUCCAGUGAACCAUCAAUUAAGAAACAAGGGAUUGUGAAGAACAAGACCUAGAUCCAGACUGAAGGGAAGGAUUUGCUGAGGAGUUCAGGCCAGCAUGGGCUGGGGUGACUUGGCCUGGAACUCUACAACAGUCAGGACAGGGAGUCCUGAAUAGGGGCACCUGCAGCUGAGUCCAUGGAUGGGGAGGGACCUGUGUAAGGCACUGAAUUUAGACUCUGCACGCAGUUCUAAGAGGUGUUCUCAACACGUUUAUGCAACUAAAAAGUGUUUAUUAACAGUGUUUUGAAACAAGUGGGAUUUUUGUUGAGGUUGUAGGAUAAUUCAGGGUCAUAUGGAGAUUUUUAUUCUAUCAGUAUUUGCCCUGUCAUGUAGAUGAGACACGUUAGAGGCAAGCCUCUGAAAAUUAGAUUGAUUUAUUUUUCUAGUCUGAACCGAGGAAAAUAACUACUUGUCUUCUAUCUCCUGGUGCUCUAAUAUAUGUAAAAUGUUGUCUUAUGGUGAGACAAUGCAUAUUAAUUUUUUAGGCACUUGAUGGAAGAAGUGGAUGAGGGAAGCAGCAUCGGUCUUUGAACCUAGGUCAGAAAGAAAUGGAAGCCAUGGUGUGAGAAUAAUGCAUCAUGGUUUGUAUGGCCUUUUUCAUGUAUUUUAACUCAACUGAUUUUCUCAGGGCCUCAUCAGUCAGUCAACGCAGUUUUCUCCAUCUCAUAGCCAAGGAGACUGAGACUCAGAUCUGCCCCUGCCCACUUUUUUUGUAGUUUUAGGGGGAAGCAUAAAUGUGGAGGAAGUAAAUGAGUGUGUUUGUUCAGGCUUAGACUUUUGUUAUUUUUUAGCCUUGCAGGGAAGGGGAGGAAAGCCAAUAACGAUGGCUAGAAUUGGAGAUAGAAUGAAUGCAAGUUGCAUUAAACUGUAAGGUUAGUCUCGGUAAGAGGUUGUUUAUAUGGUGGUGUCUUGGGUGUAUCUUACCAUGUAGCAUUCUUCGUUUUAAGAAGGAUUCCUUCCGGUGCAACAUCAGUCACAGCAUAGAAAGCCUAUGCUGCUCUGCUAGUUUGCUUGCUUGCUUGCUUGCUUGCUUGCUUUCUCCUUCCUUCCUUCCUUCCUUCCCUCCCUCCCUCCUUCCCUCCUUCCCUCCUUCCUUCCUCUCUCUUUCUCUUUCUCUCUCUCUCUGUUUUUUGUUUGUUUUUGCUUUUUUUUUUUUUUUUUUUUUAAAUUUGAGACAGGGUCUUGCUCAGUCAGCCAGGCUGGAGUGCAGUGGCGCAGUCAUGGCUCACCAGCCUUGCACUUCUUGGGCUCAAGUGAUCCUCCCACCUCAGCCUCCCAAGUAGCUGGAAUGUACCACCAUGCCCGACUAAUUUUUAAUUUUUUUUAAUGGAGACGGUUUUGCCCUGUUGCCCAGACUCAUCUCAAACUCCUGGGCUCAAGUGAUCCUCCUGCCUCUGCCUCCCAAAGUGCUGAGAUUACAAGUGUGACCCACUGCGCCUCUGCCCUGUGCCACUUUUCCACAGCUGCUUUACCUACAGCCUGGGAGUCAGGCCAGCAAAUGACGACACCCCAGGCACAGACAUGCUCUCUAGGAACUUCGAGUCAGGUAUUUCACUUUGUAAAGAACUUCCAUUUUAAUUCUAUUUUCUCCUAGUUAGAGACUCAUCUUUCUUCUGAGGGGUGCAAAUGAUUCUUUGGAGAAGUUUAAACCUGUUUUACGGUUCAAACUCAAGAUGGUAGAAACAAGUCAUAUCCAAAAGAGUGCCCCGAGCUCUAAGAGUUGUGGCUGCGCAACGUUUUUUAGGUGUCUCCGAAGUGUUAUGGCCAAGUUCAGGAUUGACCCAGAUGAGGAGAGGUUGCACUGCAUAGUGAUGAUUUGUGUUGGGGAGGAGAGCUGAAACUUUGCAAAGUGGCGUCCUGAACCAACUUGUUUUUCAGCUUCUAGGGAAAUUUGUUAGGUAAUUUUUAAAAAAAGAGAGAGAGAGACAGAGAAGACUUAAUUUGAUGGAGCCUAAACUCCACUGUCUUCUUUCUGCUGAGUGCUAAGGGGCUCAUGGUCUCUGAGGACAGAGGGCAGGAAAACACCUUCAUGCCCUGUGUCCUCUGUAAGGGGCCUCUAGUAUGAGGGACUCUGAUGACUAUUGCUGUUGGGGAAAAGAAGGAAAAGGAACAGGGGUCAACUUCUGUCAUCAUCUCUCCAGAGUUUAUGAUGUUUCUGAAAGGAUGGGGAAUAGUGCGUGGCCCCCACUCAUCCCUGUGAGGUGCUGCCCAGGUAUCCAACCUGCAGUGCACAUGCUCGCCACUGGCACUGGGGAUGGUGAGUGCAGCAGAGAGAUGGGAUUCUUAAUUUAUUCAAUUUUAAUUAAAAAACACAGUUCAGUUGUUAAAAACCUAUUUAAGUGUGUUUGGAAUAGCUUGGAUAUGUGAAUUUACCUUUUCAACUGUGAAUUUUAUGAACUCUAAAUACAGAUCAAGUAUUUCCAGCAAAAAUUUAGUGUCGGAUUUGAAAUGUGCUCUAAUGGAAACUAGACACCAGAUUUCGAAGACUUAGUAUGAAAAAAACAUAAAAUACCUCAGUAAUUAUCUGUAUUGACUAUACAUUGAAAGAAUAUUUUGGCCACAUUGAGUUAGGUGUCCUAUGUUAUUUAGAUGCAUUUUACCCAUCUCUUGUUUUUCAUGUAGCUACCAGAAAAUGUUAAAUUACCUAUGGGGCUCCCCUUAUAUUUCUGUGGGACAGUGCGAGUCUAGACAGUGCCUUACGGGAUCCAUCAGAAGCAUUAUUGGACUUUCUAGGGAAAGUUGCUGGACUUCAAAAGUUAGAGUCAUAAUUUUUCCCGUUGUGUUAACAAGUUGCUUUAUGUGGAUGGGUUUAUGACAAUUGAGGGUUGGAAAAUAGGUUUUAAUAAGAGUAAGUUAAUUGAGAGGACAGCUUUACCUCUGUUAAUCAGAAUGAUUUUAAAAUGCAUUUUCACCCACUCAGAAACCACUGAUUCUCAUGGGAACAAAAAACUACAUUCGUGCGUAGUACGAAUUUGUGCCUGCUGGGUCCUUGUACCUUUACGCCAGGCAGAAAUCUCCGUAAUCGUCAGUGUAGAUUUCAUUUCCUUGUGGCAAGGAAUAUAAAGUAAUACAACCAAAGGGGAAUUCCACUGCAUGAAAGGAAAUAUUAGUGCUCGUCUAGCUCUUGUUUCAACCCUAUAAGCUCCAAGUGAUUUUCAGAGUCCCUCCUUCAACUUUUUUGUUAAACUUUCCAGAUUUUCCUAUUUAUAGAUUUCAGUUGUUGGCAGCUACAUGUUGGAACCGUUGUUGAAGCCCCUAGUAAGACUUGAUGCUGUAGCACGCUUUCACAGCUUGGUUUGCAAGUUGCUUUCUAAAGAUGCAAAGAGAAUUACUACCCACUCUAGUAGUUUGAACAACCCAGUGAAUUUCAGAUAUUAAAGCCAUAUUCAUGCCACUGUUCUCCUAAUUCUAUCACUGUUUAGAAUUGCAUUUUGUCUAAAGGAAGGAUAGAUAGAAUACUACUAAUAAUAUCAAGAUGCUCAGAAACUGUUGAGAAUUUUUUUUACAGGAAGAACUUAAAUUUCCAGAGGCUUUUAAAAAAAAAUUUAUUAAGGAAGGAGUAAAUAAAUACGCCGGGUUCUUGAGUAAACUACUUUUACCCUUCAGAACCACUUUGUACGUAGACUUUAUCAUGAUGGCCAAGAGUUUUUAAAAUACUAUAGGCAGAGGGUAUACUCUAGAGAAAGAAGACAACAUUGGGUUUAGGACUGCUAGCCCCAUCCAGAGCAGUUAUGUGGUUCAUUCAGGGAUCUUCUUAGCCCUUCAACCUCAAUUUCUACAUCUGUGAGGUAGGUUUUGUGCUAGUUCUAGUGACAUGACUCGUGGGUGUAUUAGGAGGAUAUAGCAGCAUGUAAUUGAAGGGCUUUUAUCUUGGAAAAGCCUUAGUAGGCUCAAGGUUUCUAGUUGUUUAGGGUUCUAAGAUUUUACUAACUAGUCAGCUGCUUGGAGUUCAAGGCAUUUCUUCAGAUUAUAAUGAGUUGAUAGUGCAGUGUGCAAAAAUAAAGACCGAACCAUGGUAAGUAGCAAGGUUACUGUAAGGAAAAAAAUGUGUCCCACUGGCCCCUUUAAAAUGGCACAGGUGCAUCUCUGUAGCAACCUUGACAGCCAUCAUGUGGGAUCAUUCCCCUCACCCAGGGAACAGUGGUUCCCCAAUCUCCAAUCUCUCCAUUCUCCAGCAUGAGAAAGUGGUCUGGAGCUUGAUCACAUGAAGAUGGACAGACACAGCCUUUUGGAUGCGAGAGAGGGAAGGGAAUGCAGGCCAAAAGUGGGGUGGGUUUUCCUUUCCUCUUCCUUGUUUUUUAUUAACCUUGUCUUGCUCCUGCCACACACAAGUGCAGCCAGUGCUCAGGACACUGCUCCGUGUGGAGCUCCGGAAAGUGAAGCUGAGAAGCCUUCCUUGGGGUGGACAUGGGGGGAGCUGCAGAGGCAAUAGGGAGAAAAUAACAACCAUGGCUCAGGCACUGCUUGGAGCAGUUGUUCAUAUGUAGGUCAGGUAGUCAUCAUUCAGGAACUUCCUGUAUUACACAAAUAAUCUCUAUUUUAUGGUUAAAGGUAGGACAGUGAUAAUUUACUCAGGAGGGAAGGACAAUUAGCAAAUUGAUUAAUAAGGUUUCUAAAACCUAUUGUGAAAGAGAAUCCUUUAACAUAUGUCUUGAUUUAUUCUGCUUAUUUAUGUCUUGAUUUAAGACAGUGAUUCGCAACUUUAGCUCUGCAUAUUGCAAUCACCUGGGAGCUUUAACAGCGUUCAUGCCUGGCUCCCAUCCCUGGAGAUUUACUUGGCUAUUGGGAUUGUGUUUUAAAGUUUCUCCAGGUGAUUCUAAUACACAGAUAAUAGCCAGAAUGCCUGAUUUAAAAUGUUUCCUGAAUUGUUAGCUGAUCUUGAGUGCAUAUUUUCUAUGUACUGUUGCACACUAAUAGUUUUAAUGAAGGCACAGAAUCUUAUGUAAAAUAAACUGUUAAUUGGUCUUAACUACAGGGCUACAAGAGUUUCCUUCUUAUUUCAAGCUGCUUAAUAUUCCGUUAAUCACUGUUGUCAUGCACACACACUUCUGUAUUCCAUUCUCAUUCAUUUACUUUUUAGAAUGGUAUUAAUGCUGGUGGCAUUUGCAGGGUAGUAGUCACCUUGUCAGUAGAACUUGCUUUAGUAAUUAGUUGUCAGAAACAAAACUCCCCAGACUUUCUACCCAUGACCACAAUGAAGGGAAUGAUGCCUUUUCUGAGUCCCUAUUCCUAAGAAUCAGGAAAUUUCUAUGAUAUUUGACAAGUAUAGGUAGAAAUUACUUGCCAAGGUGAUUAUGACUUCUGGAAAAAAUUUUUUUAAAGGAAACACAGGUGUGUAACACUCCUAAUCAGUAUAUAAGAUUGUUUGUAUGUUACUUUUUCGAGUUAUAAAAGGAAGAGGAUAAAUUCUGCCUCCUUCCCCAGUUACUGUCAAUCUUCAGUCUUCUUUUGAAUUAAGUUAGUUUCCCAUUUUACAACAUAAAGACAAGUUUAAUUCUUAAGGCUUACAUAAAAAAGUAAUGUUUAAUUUGGGAUUUCUCAAAUUCUUCAUCAUAAUAACACCUUGCAUUAGUAGAGAACCUUUGUUGCAAGAAGAUCAAAAUAUUUUAUAAGCUUCAUCUCAUUUUUCUUUUCUUUCUUUCUUUUUUUUUUUUUUUUUUGGAGACAGCAUCUUGCUCUGUCGCCCUGGCUGGAGUGCAGUAGCACAAUCACAGCUCACUGUAGCCUCAACCUCCUGGGCUCAAGUGAUCCUUCCACCUCAGCCUCCCAAGUAGCUGGAACCACAGGCACAUGCCACCAUGCCUGGCUAAUUUUUCAUAUUUUUUGUAGAGACGGGGUUUCGCCAUGUUGCCCAGGCUGGUCUCGAACUACUGAGCUCGAGGGAUCCUCUUGCCCUGGCCUCCCAAAGUAUUGGGAUUACAGGUGUGAGCCACUGCGCCAGACCUCUUUUAUCUUUGAGAUAAUACCGUGUGACGACAAAGGCUGGGUAUUGUUAUCCGAAUCUCUCACACAGCAACACUGAGGAGACAUUGACUCAUUUCUUUUACGUUGCUUUUUAAGUACAGUAUUGUUUGGUUUUGUUGAAAAUUAUUUUGGUAGUAAACAUUUUCCAGAGAUAUAAAUCUUUUCCAGACUCAUUUGCGCUUGUUACUGUAGGUAGAAUUCAUGAGGCUUUUCCUAUUUCUGUUUAUUUCGGAGCCUGAAGUGACCCAGGAAUUAUGUGAUAUAUGUAGAGCGAGGGAAUUUCUUCAGUUUGACUGUGGUCCUGGUUGUAACCCAGCCUUCUUCCUUACAGAUGGGGGUGAGGGUUGGGGUAUCCCUUAGAGCCUGGUGUGUCUUCAUACAAACAGCUUUGCUGGGGCUGCCUAGAGCCUGGGCCAGCAGUGGGGUAGUAUCAAGUACAGGGCAUUAUUCAGCGGUUCUCCACACUCUCCUCAUUUGAAUGAGAAUAUAAAUCUUCUCCCCUGGCUCUCAUGUCACAUCUUUAAAACCUCAAGUUUCUUAUUAGGCAUGUGUGGUCCAUUUAAGCUCUAGACAUUUCGAAAAGAUAAAUCACAGGGCAAAACAUCUUUCUAGUUUUGAAGGAGGUCUGAGUUGCAGCUCGCUGGGGUUGUGAGUCUGAGCCGUCGCUUUUCUUUCUCUUCCUUUUACAAGACUUCCAGGAUAUAGCCGUUAAAGAAGGACACAAAAAAGAGCAAAGCCCUCAGUGAUGCUGUGGCACAAAGAAGAAAGCUACUUGAGGAGGAGGCGAAGGGUUUACGAAGAGGCAAAGAAUGCAGCAGGAACGAAUUUCAUAUACACCUCCAGAGAGCCCAGUGCCGAGUUACGCUUCCUCGACGCCACUUCAUGUUCCAGUGCCUCGAGCGCUCAGGAUGGAGGAAGACUCGAUCCGCCUGCCUGCGCACCUGCGCUUGCAGCCAAUUUACUGGAGCAGGGAUGACGUAGCCCAGUGGCUCAAGUGGGCUGAAAAUGAGUUUUCUUUAAGGCCAAUUGACAGCAACACGUUUGAAAUGAAUGGCAAAGCUCUCCUGCUGCUGACCAAAGAGGACUUUCGCUAUCGAUCUCCUCAUUCAGGUGAUGUGCUCUAUGAACUCCUUCAGCAUAUUCUGAAGCAGAGGAAACCUCGGAUUCUUUUUUCACCAUUCUUCCACCCUGGAAACUCUAUACACACACAGCCGGAGGUCAUACUGCAUCAGAACCAUGAAGAAGAUAACUGUGUCCAGAGGACCCCCAGGCCAUCCGUGGAUAAUGUGCACCAUAACCCUCCCACCAUUGAACUGUUGCACCGCUCCAGGUCACCUAUCACGACAAAUCACCGGCCUUCUCCUGACCCCGAGCAGCGGCCCCUCCGGUCCCCCCUGGACAACAUGAUCCGCCGCCUCUCCCCGGCUGAGAGAGCUCAGGGACCCAGGCCGCACCAGGAGAACAACCACCAGGAGUCCUACCCUCUGUCAGUGUCUCCCAUGGAGAAUAAUCACUGCCCAGCGUCCUCCGAGUCCCACCCGAAGCCAUCCAGCCCCCGGCAGGAGAGCACACGCGUGAUCCAGCUGAUGCCCAGCCCCAUCAUGCACCCUCUGAUCCUGAACCCCCGGCACUCCGUGGAUUUCAAACAGUCCAGGCUCUCCGAGGACGGGCUGCAUAGGGAAGGGAAGCCCAUCAACCUCUCUCAUCGGGAAGACCUGGCUUACAUGAACCACAUCAUGGUCUCUGUCUCCCCGCCUGAAGAGCACGCCAUGCCCAUUGGGAGAAUAGCAGACUGUAGACUGCUUUGGGAUUACGUCUAUCAGUUGCUUUCUGACAGCCGGUACGAAAACUUCAUCCGAUGGGAGGACAAAGAAUCCAAAAUAUUCCGGAUAGUGGAUCCCAACGGACUGGCUCGACUGUGGGGAAACCAUAAGAACAGAACAAACAUGACCUAUGAGAAAAUGUCCAGAGCCCUGCGCCACUACUACAAACUAAACAUUAUCAGGAAGGAGCCAGGACAAAGGCUUUUGUUCAGGUUUAUGAAAACCCCAGAUGAAAUCAUGAGUGGCCGAACAGACCGUCUGGAGCACCUAGAGUCCCAGGAGCUGGAUGAACAAAUAUACCAAGAAGAUGAAUGCUGAAGGAACCAACAGUCCACCUCAGCGGGCCAGCAGCCCAGGGAACCCCUGCCCACCAGGAUUGCUGGAAGUGUGACGGAGCAGGCGGGCUGAGGAGAGUGGAAAAGGAAGCGACCCAGAAAUGGCAGGGACACUUCUCUUGCAGACCAAGAGGGACCCUGGAGCACCUUAGACAAACUACCCAGCACAGGCGGGGCUGGAAUUCUGGCGGAGGGCAUGAGCCUGGGACUCCAUGUCACGUUUCCUUCUGAUUUGGAAUCUCUCCAUCUGUAAUUCCUCACCCUCACCCUUCCACCGUUGUUAGUAUCAUGGUGUUUUUGUUUUUGUUUUUGUUUUAAGAACCUGCAGUUUGACUCUUCAUCGUUCAUCUAGGGGAAGACAUCUGAUGUUGUUUUCCUAUGGAAAUAUAUAUCUAUUAUAUAUAUAUUUUUUGCAAAUCUCACAAAGUGCGGCAAGCCCAGCUGGUCAGGAAAGAGAAUACUUGCAGAGGGGUUCAGGUUCCUCUUUUUCCUGCCACGUGGAUCAGGUCUGUUCCUGUUACUGUUGGGUCUUGGCUGAAAAAAAAAAAUGCUUUUAAAAAAGAUAAAAUGAAAAGGAGAGCUCUCUUUUUCUCUCUCUUGCUCUGUUCUUCCCUUGGUCCCCUCUGUCCUCCCGCCCUGCCUGCAGUUGAGAUUCAGAUGCCUUCUGACAGAGUUCAGCCUCUUGGAGAGUCUUGGGGAUUGUUGGCACCUAAACAGAAUCAGUGACCCGGGUGCUUUGUGGCCAGCAGCACAGAAUCAAACCCGCAUCCCAGCAUUGGGCCACCCAUCUGAGGGAGGCCAAAAUCAUCACAGAUGCUGCUGUGCUGCAGACAGAUACAUGCUAGUCCAGAGAGCCGCCCCUGAGAUGGCUGUGAGAACCAUGUGUCUAAGGCGUAAGAUAAGGAUGGAAGGCUGUCCAAGUUAUUUGGAAGGCCUCGGCAGCUUGGGAUUAGCUUGGGAGCGCAGCGCUGCAAAGUGGAAAAUAUGAAAAGACCACACAGGCCCAGCAGUCCAGAAACUGGGCAAAAAUAUUCUGCAGUGGGGAUUUAUUUUUCCAAAGCAGGUAACAGAGGCUAGUGAGAAAGAAAAGCUCCUCUCUGCUCCAUUCCAAAGGCCAUCUUGUGGUCAGUUUCAUGCCCUCACCUGAUUUUUUUUUUUUUUUUUUUUUUUCAAUUCCUAACCUUUUUUAAAGUUUCCUGGUCUCCACUGGACACAGAGCUUUGGAGACGGAGGAUCCCAGAGGGCAGUCUCAGUUGCAAUCAGUGUGUGCCCAGCCUGGGCAGACAGGAAAUUCCUCGGAUACAUUAUUUUUUCUUUCUUUCAUAGCUGUGUCUCAGAAAGGACCCAUUUGUGGCUCUUUUUCACCUCAAAAUAAGAUCGAUGGUAUCUUGUAAAAUGAGGGUAGUGCCACUUCUUAGUAUUUUUGAAAGCUGUUUUAGAUUUUUUUUUUUUUUCCUUUUCUAGCCAUCUAAAUUGACUCUUCCAAUAUAGGUCUCAGAAAUCCAAUAUUUGGAGUACAAUUUCUUUUAAUCCAGAUUACACCUGCCUUACAAAGCACCCCCUCCUUGUUCCCCUCUGUUUCCUCUACUCAGUUGGGGGAGAAACUCACAGCUCCUCCGGGAUACAUAUGUGCCCUCAGCAGCAGCUCCCAGGUGAAGUUACCAGACCCCUGGGCUUCUCCCCAGCUUUUUCUGAGUUGAGUCAGACAUGUAGAGUUUGGGUCACACAGGCAAGAGGAAUUUUCCCUCGGCCUUACUGACAAGGACACCAACCUAGGGUGCAAACAGAUGGACUAUGGUUCAAGGACACUGGAAUUGAGGAGCUGAUCAAGGCUCUCUUCAGCCUUGCUCUGUCCCUGCCUCUUAUCAGAGCACAGGUAGACACACGGGCAUAGCCAGCCCACUCCUACUGUCACAGGCGCCCCACCAUUCAACCUUCCGGGAGGUCAGGGACCUUCUAUAUGAGGCGAGUGGGUCUCAGUCUGCUUGAAUGGUGAUGAGAUUCUGCUGGAUCUCAGCACGCUGCAGGUGUCUUUUGAGAGCAUUCAGUAGGACAUGGUGAUCCCUAUUUCAGCCUCUAAGAUGACUGGUAUUCUAUCUGAAAUGCAGAGAUUAAGCCAAAUACCUGAUGUAUUGUGAAAGCCACUGAUUUUAAGAAUGGAGAGAAAGGGAUUUUUUACUGCAUCCCUCUGUAUGAAUAUGAAAUCAGAGACCAGGGCAUGAUGUUGCUAGGAUUAGAGCCUCUCAGUCUGGCCUCUUCACCCAAGUGCAAGAACUCAGUCUCUUACUGUUCAAAGAAUCUUAACAGUUGAAUUAUGGAGGGAAAUUCCCUUUUGCCCCAAGCAUUUCUAUAUUUAAAGCAAUAUCCCAGGAGAAUAUGUUAGACUUAGGAUGAUACCUUCAGCCACUUGAAGAAGAAAUAGAAGGCGCUCAUUCCAAUAUAGUCUUUAUUUCCCAUUCAGAUACAGGUUGAGCAUCCCUAAUCUGAACAGUUAAAACCCCCAAAUGCCCCAAAAUCCAAACCUUCCUGAACGCUAUGACACCAUGAGUGGAAAAUUCCACACCUAACAAACACAUUUGCUUUCUUAUGGUUCAAUGUACACAAACUGUUUUAUAUAGAAAAUGAUUUCAAAUAUCAUAAAAUUACCUUCAGGCUAUGUGUAUAAAGUAUAUAUGAGCCAUAAAUGAAUUUUGUGUUUAGACUUUGUGUCCAUCCCCAAGAUCUCUCAUUUUAUAUAUAUAUAUAUAUAUAUAUAUAUAUAUAUAUAUAUAUAUAUAUACACACACACACACAUACACAAAUAUUCCAGGAUACAAAAAAAAACAUUUAAAAAUCCGAGACCCAGAACACUUCUGGUCCCAAGCAUUUCAGAUAAGGGAUAUCAAUCUGUACUACCAAUAAGGAUUUCGUAAUUCCCCUAACUGCAAAUGUCCUCUUCAUUUGUUCUUUAUGAGAAAACCCGGGUAGUGCCAGCACCUGGAUACAGUAUUUACACCCUGCAGACCCUAAAGAUUUCAGAUUCAGUUAGCAAACCUUGAUGAAGCACCUGCUGGACACUGAGGGACCCAAAGCUCAAUCAGCCAUAAUCCCUGCUUUCAGAGUUUAUAUUGUACCUGCCUAAUCCACCCGGCGUGACUCAUUUCAACACUAAGUACUAGGGGUGUUGUCAGGAGACAAAUCUGAAGUCAGGAGAGGAAAAUGCAAAGGAGCCCUGCCGUGUGAUGGAUGUGCAUUCUCACUUGGGUCUUGAAGUUCUCAUUCCUACAUCUCAAGCUAGCCAGGCAGUCUCCUCUCUAUCAGAAGAAAGCACUGGUAAUUGGCUAGACUGGCUAUGUUGAAGGUAACAUGAACUCUAAGAUCUUGACCCAGGGCGACUUGGUUUUGCUUAAGGUGGCAUCACCAAUGUUCCAAAUCCUUUAGGGAGAUGAGGGUAUCCCCACAGAAAAAGAGGAAUAAUAGACCAAUGGAUUUUCUCCUUUCACCAGUAUGUUUGGAACCCUCUGAUCCAAUGUCUUUUGAUACUGAUCUCUUGUCCAAAUGAGAAUGUCGCUUUAGCUGAAAUUCAAAUGGCUGUGACAAUUUACCGAAAUGAUGAAGUAACCACCAUUCCCACCUUUCACUGCCUAGGCUCCAAGUCUGAAUACAUUUUUGAAAUAGGAACUCCCUUUUGCAAAAAAGAAACCUGGGUGUCAGGGAGGUGAAGUGACUUGCCCUAGGAGCAGACAGCAUGCCAAGAAUGGAAUUAGGCUCAGGAUCCAGCCUGGGCUCACCCUGUGUGGCUCAUUCCCACCCAGGAAACUGAAGAUAAAAGAUUUGGGAAAACACACCAAGAAAAAGGGGCAGUUUUCUUUGCCCAAGCAUUUGGUGCUAGUUAGAGGCUGUUCACUCUCUCCUGCUCCUCUUCGGAGUAGAAAUAAAGGCUGUGACACAAGGAAGCCAGUGGGGUGGGAGGGAGGCACCAUAAUCCCUCCCUAAAACCCACAGAAGACUAACCUGAUACUCUUUUGACCCAACUGCAUCAACACUAAACAGCUGCAGACCCCCUGAAUCUUUCACACAUGCCAAGUGAACAUUCUUGAUGAUUUCUCUUUGUGACCGCAACCACCUGCAAACCAGAACGACUCUAGAAUUUCCUUCCCCGCCCCCCUUUUUGUUUAGUUUCUAAUCUCUUGUUUAUGAGGUGUGGGGUUUAUAAGGGACUGAAUCAAAUGAAUGUAACAAAAAAGAAAAAAAAAACAAAAAAAAAUGCCUUUUCUCAGGGCCAGUGAGUUGCAAAUAAUUUUUAAAGAAAAGCCUAUAAUUACAUCAUCUCAA